GUCAUUGGCUCUGGGAAGCGGCAGCAGAGGCAGGGACCACUCGGGGUCUGGUGUCGGCACAGCCAUGGCGGGCGCGUUGGUGCGGAAAGCGGCGGACUAUGUCCGAAGCAAGGAUUUCCGGGACUACCUCAUGAGCCCUGGGUUCAUGCAUGAUAAAGUAGACAGCAACACCACCAUACAGUGCAGAGGAGUGGCAAGAGAGUAAACGGAAAAGGAGAUGAAAAUAGACCAAGUGGAGAAAGGCCUGGUCAAAAAAGGAGGAAAAGGAAGAUCACUAUGGAAUAAUAGAGAGUUGAAAAAUGAAGUGACACCCAAUAACAGGACGGGACAAUCAGAGAUGACUUGGUUGUAGUGUGGAAACCAGUAGGGACCUUGGGAAGCUGCCAAACCCUUUCUAGCUCUGGGCUCAGCUGUAAGAACUGCUGAUUCCUACAGGAACACUUGGACAAUCCAAUACCUAAAUGUUAACCAUCAAUUAACCCAGUAAACCUGCAAGAUGGAAACGAAGAUUUGUUCUCACGAGUUUCACGUGAUUAUUUAAACACUUCUGGGGCCCAGUAGCCAACUGGGGUCUUCCCAUUGCUGCCAUCAAUGAUAUGAAAAAGUCUCCAGAGAUUAUCAGUGGGCGGAUGACAUUUGCCCUCUGUUGCUAUUCUUUGACAUUCAUGAGAUUUGCCUACAAGGUACAGCCUCGGAACUGGCUUCUGUUUGCAUGCCACGCAACAAAUGAAGUAGCCCAGCUCAUCCAGGGAGGGCGGCUUAUCAAACACGAGAUGACUAAAACGGCAUCUGCAUAACAAUGGAAAAGGAAGAACAAGGUCUUGAAGGGACAGCAUUGCCAGCUGCUGCUGAGUCACAGAUUUCAUUAUAAAUAGCCUCCCUAAGGAAAAUACACUGAAUGCUAUUUUUACUAACCAUUCUAUUUUUAUAGAAAUAGCUGAGAGUUUCUAAACCAACUCUCUGCUGCCUUACAAGUAUUAAAUAUUUUACUUCUUUCCAUAAAGAGUAGCUCAAAAUAUGCAAUUAAUUUAAUAAUUUCUGAUGAUGGUUUUAUCUGCAGUAAUAUGUAUAUCAUCUAUUAGAAUUUACUUAAUGAAAAACUGAAGAGAACAAAAUUUGUAACCACUAGCACUUAAGUACUCCUGAUUCUUAACAUUGUCUUUAAUGACCACAAGACAACCAACAGCUGGCCACGUACUUAAAAUUUUGUCCCCACUGUUUAAAAAUGUUACCUGUGUAUUUCCAUGCAGUGUAUAUAUUGAGAUGCUGUAACUUAAUGGCAAUAAAUGAUUUAAAUAUUUGUUAAA